CCUCUCGGCUUUCGGCUCGGAGGAGGCCAAGGUGCAACUUCCUUCGGUCGUCCCGAAUCCGGGUUCAUCCGACACCAGCCGCCUCCACCAUGCCGCCGAAGUUCGACCCCAACGAGAUCAAAGUCGUAUACCUGAGGUGCACCGGAGGUGAAGUCGGUGCCACUUCUGCCCUGGCCCCCAAGAUCGGCCCCCUGGGUCUGUCUCCAAAAAAAGUUGGUGAUGACAUUGCCAAGGCAACGGGUGACUGGAAGGGCCUGAGGAUUACAGUGAAACUGACCAUUCAGAACAGACAGGCCCAGAUUGAGGUGGUGCCUUCUGCCUCUGCCCUGAUCAUCAAAGCCCUCAAGGAACCACCAAGAGACAGAAAGAAACAGAAAAACAUUAAACACAGUGGGAAUAUCACUUUUGAUGAGAUUGUCAACAUUGCUCGACAGAUGCGGCACCGAUCCUUAGCCAGAGAACUCUCUGGAACCAUUAAAGAGAUCCUGGGGACUGCCCAGUCAGUGGGCUGUAAUGUUGAUGGCCGCCAUCCUCAUGACAUCAUCGAUGACAUCAACAGUGGUGCUGUGGAAUGCCCAGCCAGUUAAGCACAAAGGAAAACAUUUCAAUAAAGGAUCAUUUGACAACUGGUGGA